CUCUCAGCAACCCGCACAGGGCGCACCCGGACGCUCUACCGCUCCCGCCGCAGUCGCCGGGCCAUGGGCCUCGAGCCCGCCCCGAACCCCCGCGAGCCCGCCUUGUCUGCGGCGUGACUGGAGGCCCAGAUGGUCAUCAUGGGCCAGUGCUACUACAACGAGACCAUCGGCUUCUUCUAUAACAACAGUGGCAAAGAGCUCAGCUCCCACUGGCGGCCCAAGGAUGUGGUCGUGGUGGCACUGGGGCUGACCGUCAGCGUGCUGGUGCUGCUGACCAAUCUGCUGGUCAUAGCAGCCAUCGCCUCCAACCGCCGCUUCCACCAGCCCAUCUACUACCUGCUCGGCAAUCUGGCCGCGGCUGACCUCUUCGCGGGCGUGGCCUACCUCUUCCUCAUGUUCCACACUGGUCCCCGCACAGCCCGACUUUCACUUGAGGGCUGGUUCCUGCGGCAGGGCUUGCUGGACACAAGCCUCACUGCGUCGGUGGCCACACUGCUGGCCAUCGCCGUGGAGCGGCACCGCAGUGUGAUGGCCGUGCAGCUGCACAGCCGCCUGCCCCGUGGCCGCGUGGUCAUGCUCAUUGUGGGCGUGUGGGUGGCUGCCCUGGGCCUGGGGCUGCUGCCUGCCCACUCCUGGCACUGCCUCUGUGCCCUGGACCGCUGCUCACGCAUGGCACCCCUGCUCAGCCGCUCCUAUUUGGCCGUCUGGGCUCUGUCGAGCCUGCUUGUCUUCCUGCUCAUGGUGGCUGUGUACACCCGCAUUUUCUUCUACGUGCGGCGGCGAGUGCAGCGCAUGGCAGAGCAUGUCAGCUGCCACCCCCGCUACCGAGAGACCACGCUCAGCCUGGUCAAGACUGUUGUCAUCAUCCUGGGGGCGUUCGUGGUCUGCUGGACACCAGGCCAGGUGGUACUGCUCCUGGAUGGUUUAGGCUGUGAGUCCUGCAAUGUCCUGGCUGUAGAAAAGUACUUCCUACUGUUGGCCGAGGCCAACUCCCUGGUCAAUGCUGCUGUGUACUCUUGCCGAGAUGCUGAGAUGCGCCGCACCUUCCGCCGCCUUCUCUGCUGCGCGUGCCUCCGCCAGUCCACCCGCGAGUCUGUCCACUAUACAUCCUCUGCCCAGGGAGGUGCCAGCACUCGCAUCAUGCUUCCCGAGAACGGCCACCCACUGAUGGACUCCACCCUUUAGCUACCUUGAACUUCAGCGGUACGCGGCAAGCAACAAAUCCACAGCCCCUGAUGACUUGUGGGUGCUCCUGGCUCAACCCAACCAACAGGACUGACUGACUGGCAGGACAAGGUCUGGCAUGGCACAGCACCACUGCCAGGCCUCCCCAGGCACACCACUCUGCCCAGGGAAUGGGGGCUUUGGGUCAUCUCCCACUGCCUGGGGGAGUCAGAUGGGGUGCAGGAAUCUGGCUCUUCAGCCAUCUCAGGUUUAGGGGGUUUGUAACAGACAUUAUUCUGUUUUCACUGCGUAUCCUUGGUAAGCCCUGUGGACUGGUUCCUGCUGUGUGAUGCUGAGGGUUUUAAGGUGGGGAGAGAUAAGGGCUCUCUCGGGCCAUGCUACCCGGUAUGACUGGGUAAUGAGGACAGACUGUGGACACCCCAUCUACCUGAGUCUGAUUCUUUAGCAGCAGAGACUGAGGGGUGCAGAGUGUGAGCUGGGAAAGGUUUGUGGCUCCUUGCAGCCUCCAGGGACUGGCCUGUCCCCGAUAGAAUUGAAGCAGUCCACGGGGAGGGGAUGAUACAAGGAGUAAACCUUUCUUUACACUCUGAGGUCUCCAAAA